AGAGCAGAGCAGGACACUGGCGCCGCGGGUCAGGCAGCUGCGUGCGCGUCUCCUCCAGGCAGCAAGGGGAACCCGAGGCCGCCGGCGCCCGGACCAUGUCGUCUCCGGGGCCGUCGCAGCCGCCGGCCGAGGACCCGCCCUGGCCCGCGCGCCUCCUGCGUGCGCCUCUGGGGCUGCUGCGGCUGGACCCCAGCGGGGGCGCGCUGCUGCUAUGCGGCCUCGUAGCGCUGCUGGGCUGGAGCUGGCUGCGGAGGCGCCGGGCGCGGGGCAUCCCGCCCGGGCCCACGCCCUGGCCUCUGGUGGGCAACUUCGGUCACGUGCUGCUGCCUCCCUUCCUCCGGCGGCGGAGCUGGCUGAGCAGCAGGACCAGGGCCGCAGGGAUUGAUCCCUCGGUCAUAGGCCCGCAGGUGCUCCUGGCUCACCUAGCCCGCGUGUACGGCAGCAUCUUCAGCUUCUUUAUCGGCCACUACCUGGUGGUGGUCCUCAGCGACUUCCACAGCGUGCGCGAGGCGCUGGUGCAGCAGGCCGAGGUCUUCAGCGACCGCCCGCGGGUGCCGCUCAUCUCCAUCGUGACCAAGGAGAAGGGUGAGCGGGAGGUCGUGGGCUGUGGGUACGCGGAUGCCGCGGAUGAGUCUCCAGGGGUUGUGUUUGCACAUUAUGGUCCCGUCUGGAGACAACAAAGGAAGUUCUCUCAUUCAACUCUUCGUCAUUUUGGGUUGGGAAAACUUAGCUUGGAGCCCAAGAUUAUUGAGGAGUUCAAAUAUGUGAAAGCAGAAAUGCAAAAGCACGGAGAAGACCCCUUCUGCCCUUUCUCCAUCAUCAGCAAUGCCGUCUCUAACAUCAUUUGCUCCUUGUGCUUUGGCCAGCGCUUUGAUUACACUAAUAGUGAGUUCAAGAAAAUGCUUGGUUUUAUGUCACGAGGCCUAGAAAUCUGUCUGAACAGUCAAGUCCUCCUGGUCAACAUAUGCCCUUGGCUUUAUUACCUUCCCUUUGGACCAUUUAAGGAAUUAAGACAAAUUGAAAAGGAUAUAACCAGUUUCCUUAAAAAAAUCAUCAAAGACCAUCAAGAGUCUCUGGAUAGAGAGAACCCUCAGGACUUCAUAGACAUGUACCUUCUCCACAUGGAAGAGGAGAGGAAAAAUAAUAGUAACAGCAGUUUUGAUGAAGAGUACUUAUUUUAUAUCAUUGGGGAUCUCUUUAUUGCUGGGACUGAUACCACAACUAACUCUUUGCUCUGGUGCCUGCUGUAUAUGUCGCUGAACCCCGAUGUACAAGAAAAGGUUCAUGAAGAAAUUGAAAGAGUCAUUGGCGCCAACCGAGCUCCUUCCCUCACAGACAAGGCCCAGAUGCCCUACACAGAAGCCACCAUCAUGGAAGUGCAGAGGCUAACUGUGGUGGUGCCGCUUGCCAUUCCUCAUAUGACCUCAGAGAACACAGUGCUCCAAGGGUAUACCAUUCCUAAAGGCACAUUGAUCUUACCCAACCUGUGGUCAGUACAUAGAGACCCAGCCAUUUGGGAGAAACCGGAGGAUUUCUACCCUAAUCGAUUUCUGGAUGACCAAGGACAACUAAUUAAAAAAGAAACCUUUAUUCCUUUUGGGAUAGGGAAGCGGGUGUGUAUGGGAGAACAACUGGCAAAGAUGGAAUUAUUCCUAAUGUUUGUGAGCCUAAUGCAGAGUUUCGCAUUUGCUUUACCUGAGGAUUCUAAGAAGCCCCUCCUGACUGGAAGAUUUGGUCUAACUUUAGCCCCACAUCCAUUUAAUAUAACUAUUUCAAGGAGAUGAAGAGCAUCUCCAAGAAGAGAUGGUAAAAAGAUAUAUAAAUACAUAUCCUUCUAAGCAGAUUCUUCCUACUGCAAAGGACAGUGAAUCCAGCAACUCAGUGGAUCCAAGCUGGGCUCAGAGGUCGGAAGGAGGGUAGAGCACACUGGGAGGUUUCAUCUUGGAGGAUUCCUCAGCAGGAUACUUCAGCCAUUUUAGUAAUGCAGGUCUGUGAUUUGGGGGAUAGAAAACAAAGUACCUAUGAAACGGGAUAUCUGGAUUUUACUUGCAGUGGCUUCCACCGAUGGGCCAAUCUUCUCAUUUCUUAGUGCCUCAGACAUCCCAUAUGUAAAAUGAGAGUAAUAAAACUUGGCUUCUCUCUACCUCUCAGCACUAAUGAUGGUCAAAUGCCUUACAUCUUUUCUGAUAUCUCUAAAAUGCUGUUAAGUUCUGGAGAAGAACUUCAGGAGAAGAAGAUCUAUCAGCUGGCUUUUAAAGACCUAUGACAACAUGAAAGUGGUGUUCAGCCUGGAAUGCUUUGUCAGAGAUGGGUGUGGAUUUAGGUUAUACUGGGGGAGAACUUUUCUCAGCACAGAUUCUAUGCCAGCUUCUUUGGGCUUGUUCUGUCACUAUCUUUUUGUUUAUGAUUUUAGUUUUUACUUUUUGUAGAUGUGGGAUGAAGUGGACUCUGUCGUGUAUAUUGAGGAAAAAAGAAAUUAUAAUUUUAAAAAAUCCCUUGUAGGAUUAUUAUCUAAAUUUAUAUGUCUAACUUCUACUACAACUACAGGAACAGUGAGCCUUGCUACUUCUUUAGUAGCUUCUUGGCAGAAUUCCUUUCUACUGAGUUAUUUGCAAAGAUGCAGCUCUACCUUUUUACUUAAGGCCUGAAUGGUGAGCAUGGGGAUUUUGAUACUGGGACUCAUCAGGAAAGGAUUCUGCUUUCAAACUAUACUGAACAUUCCUGUCCUAGCGUCCCUGCCACCAGGCCCAAUGCAUCUGAUCCUUGAAUAUACUCUCAAAGAAUUCACUCUCUUUUUAUUAAGAGAACUAAAUUGUUUCUAAAUGUAGAUGGUCCCUCUGGAAAAGCAGUUUUCAGCAGGGGUGGUAACCCCUUCAGAGGGAGUUUGGAAAUGUGUGGGUAUGAUUCUUGGUUAUCAUAAUGAUGGGGGUGCUACUGGCCUUCUGCUGCCAUGGGACCAGGAUGCUAAAUGUCAAGGUAGUCCUAUACAGUGAAGAAUUGUCCUGCUCAAGAUGCCAGGAUUUCCCCCAGUGAGAACAUGCUCUAAGGAAUGACCACCCCUUUCUUUUAUUCUCCCACAGUGCUCCAUGUACAGAAGUAAGCAUAGCAGUCAUAUGAGCAACCACAUUCCUGAACCUUUCCUCAUGCUGGCUCUACACUUAAUCCUUUACUUGUAUGUUUCUGUAAUUCUUACAUAAAUUCUAUUAAGAGGGUGGCAUACUGUAGUGGAUGAAGCUGAGGCUUAUAGUAGGUAAGGCACAAAGUUAAAAAGUAACAUCACUGGGUUUCAAACCUACUGGUCUCUGUGACUAAAGAACACUUUCAGAACCACUUCUUGAUUCUGCCACCACUUGAUCCCAUAACAGGCUACCCCUUGGCCUCAUGCUGGAGUUGUGUGUGUCUGUCUUCAUCCCAGGCUGAGCUCCUUGAGGUGAGGAUGUUGUGCUGUUUGCCUCCCUCACAGUGCCUUGGUCUUAGUGGAUGCCCAGUUGUCUUGUGAAUGACUUUUAAGAAGUGUACUUAAGAGAAAAAUCCUACCUUAUUUGAAUAAUUACAAGUCAUGUUUUUGUUGCUUAAAGGUGAUAAAUCAGUGUAUAUUAUUUGUUAAUGUCCAUUAAAGCCAGUUUUUAAAAAAAUCACUGGACUUUUGUGUUUACCAUUUAAAACAACCAUUUUAAACAAACUUAGAACGAUGCCUUAGCUGUUUAUAGGUAACAGAAUGUAAACUCCCACCACCUGGAGACUAGGCCAUAUCCAGGGACCUCACACUGACUUUCCUAAAGGAGAGAAGCAGCUACGCUGUUCAUACUGAUAGAGAAGAGGGCAAGAAAAGAUCCAGAGUGGCUGUUACUUUGAAAAUUAAACGAAAGAUGAAAUUCUGAACUUAAAACACUUCUGUUUGGCCUUCUAUAACUGAUCACCCUUCUUUGCUCUGUUUUCCAGAUAAAUGGAGACACCAGAUCUCCCUAACCUCUGACUUCUGCCGUUAGCCAUACUCUGUGUAGUUAGAUCUCAGUCUGGGAAUGGCAUUCCAGGGCAAUUGUGAACAUGAGGCUAGAUUUUUCCUUUGAUUUAGCACAUUCCUAGGCAGACUUUUGCAAGCUCAAAAAAUGAAAAUAAUAUCUGCUUAACCAAAACAUAAUCAUAGGAAGAAGAAAAAUUUUAAAAUGAUUGAUUUUUGACUCUACAUUCUUUAUCUACCAUACUGCUCUUUUCCUUUUUAGAAAUAUUACUAAGCACUUUCCGUAUAGAUAAAUGAAAUACAGGCUAAUCUUUAGGUGUCUUAGGAAUUUUUGCUUUUUGAAAAAGAAAAGCUAAUAGCCUAACUGCAGAGGAACUGAGUGGAUGGGGUAGCUGCUGUAUAGAUUUUUAGAUGAGAUGAUACAGUGUGGAUUACACUGUACCUUGGGCGGGAGAGUUUGUUCUUGAUAUGGAAUUCAUAUGCUUUUGAAUUGCACUAAUAACUCAGCAUUAACAAGUAUAUUACUCCUUAAAUUAUACAUGCAUUUUCAAUAUUCCUAACCAAAUAGUUUAUAGCUUAUUGAGAAGAAGUCUGUUCUUGGAGAGAUGUUGAAAUUAGAUGUUUAUUAAACUUUAAAAUAUAAUGCCUUAAGCUGUGGCACUUUAAAAACAUCUUUAUAUAUAAAUUGCUAAAAGGACUGUUAAUGCUUUUCUCAGACACAUUGGCAUUUUACAAUUUUGCACAUGGUUUAUUUGAAAUCAAAAAAUAACUAUACUUUGUUUUAUAAGUCUACCUAAUAUCUCAUUUUUGAUUCUCAUCGUUAGCACAGUUUUGUUGCUUUUAUUAAACUAUUUUAACUGA